GUCACGCUUUGGUUUCCGGGUCGGUUCUGGCAGGUCUGAGCGCUCCGACUUCCAGAGGAGCGCUGUGCACGUGGAGAAGAGCGGGGACUCGGCGACCCUGCCCUCCCGACCCUCAUGUUCGAAGAGCCUGAGUGGGCCGAGGCGGCCCCAGUAGCCGCGGGCCUUGGGCCCGUAAUCUCACGACCUCCGCCUGCGGCCUCCUCGCAAAACAAGGGCUCCAAGCGCCGCCAGCUCUUGGCCACAUUACGGGCCCUAGAGGCAGCAUCUCUUUCCCAGCAUCCCCCCAGCCUAUGUAUAAGUGACUCUGAGGAGGAGGAGGAGGAAAGGAAGAAGAAAUGCCCCAAAAAGGCAUCAUUUGCCAGUGCCUCUGCUGAAGUAGGGAAGAAAGGGAAGAAGAAAUGUCAAAAACAGGGCCCACCUUGCAGUGACUCUGAGGAAGAAGUAGAAAGGAAGAAGAAAUGCCACAAACAGGCUCUUGUUGGCAGUGACUCUGCUGAAGAUGAGAAAAGAAAGAGGAAAUGCCAGAAACAUGCCCCUAUAAAUUCAGCCCAGCACCUGGACAAUGUUGACCAAACAGGUCCCAAAGCCUGGAAGGGUAGUACUACAAAUGAUCCACCAAAGCAAAGCCCUGGGUCCACUUCCCCUAAACCCCCUCAUACAUUAAGCCGCAAGCAGUGGCGGAACCGGCAAAAGAACAAGAGAAGAUGUAAGAACAAGUUUCAGCCACCUCAGGUGCCAGACCAGGCCCCAGCUGAGGCCCCCACAGAGAAGACAGAGGUGUCUCCUGUUCCCAGGACAGACAGCCAUGAGGCUCGGGCAGGGGCUUUGCGAGCCCGCAUGGCACAGCGGCUGGAUGGGGCCCGAUUUCGCUACCUCAAUGAACAGUUGUACUCAGGGCCCAGCAGUGCUGCACAGCGUCUCUUCCAGGAAGACCCUGAGGCUUUUCUUCUCUACCACCGCGGCUUCCAGAGCCAAGUGAAGAAGUGGCCACUGCAGCCAGUGGACCGCAUCGCCAGGGAUCUUCGCCAGCGGCCUGCAUCCCUAGUGGUGGCUGACUUCGGCUGUGGGGAUUGCCGCUUGGCUUCAAGUAUCCGGAACCCUGUGCAUUGCUUUGACUUGGCUUCUCUGGACCCUAGGGUCACUGUGUGUGACAUGGCCCAGGUUCCUCUGGAGGAUGAGUCUGUGGAUGUGGCUGUGUUUUGCCUUUCACUGAUGGGAACCAACAUCAGGGACUUCCUAGAGGAGGCAAAUAGAGUACUGAAGCCAGGGGGUCUCCUGAAAGUGGCUGAGGUCAGCAGCCGCUUUGAGGAUGUUCGAACCUUUCUGCGGGCUGUGACCAAGCUAGGCUUCAAGAUUGUCUCCAAGGACCUGACCAACAGCCAUUUCUUCUUGUUUGAUUUCCAAAAGACUGGGCCCCCUCUGGUAGGGCCCAAGGCUCAGCUUUCAGGCCUGCAGCUUCAGCCAUGUCUCUACAAGCGCAGGUGACCUCUGGAUCUUCCUUGAAAGGGGAGGCAGAUCUCAAACUCCAGGCUCAGAACUGUGAAGACUGUUUCCAGCCUGGCUGUGAGCCAAGACCUGGUUCCUGGUGGACCCUGAGGACAAAGUGUGAUAAAACCUCUGGCUCAGACUUGCUCUACUGAAGGCUUCUUGGUUAUAAGAUGCAUAAAGUCACUGGGGCUAGCUAAACAAUAAAGAGUUUAUUGUGAGAACAUGGGGAUAUCUGUCUCAUGACACUUCAGGUGUUAUGAAAACUAGAUGGUUUGGAAUUCAAGGCAUCUUUAGGUUUUGCUCUUCUUUCCAACUAAGAAGCCACAUGGCCUUCCUGUCCUGCCAUCUCCACUCUGCUGUCAUCUGAUCUGUCUACAGAUCAGCUUCCUCUGCUCACCCAUAGCUUCUGCUCCUUCAGCUUCAGUUUGCCCAGGCCUUCAAGGUUGCAGACAGGCAGCUGUUGCUGUUUGACUCUGAGGCAACUGGUUGUCCACCAACAUCUUGGCUCAAGACAUCAGUCUGAGCCACCAACUUGAGACUGUUUGGUUGUCCCCAUACCGAGCAUUUCUAGUGGUUUAUCUUUCCCCUCUCCCCUCAUCUCCAUUUUUGGAACCAUAUAGCAUCAAGCCACUCCCAACACCUAUUGUCCUGUGGGACUUUGGGAUGUAUAUAGCUGAGAGCACAGAUUUUGGAAUCAGGUAGACCUGGAUUUAAUUCUUGGCCUGCUACCCAGAGGCACUUAAAGUCAUUUAAUCUCUGUAUAUCACAUUCCUCAUUUGGAAAAUGGUAGAAUUUUUGUCUUGCAGGGUGGUUGUGUGGGUUAACUGGAGAAAUCUGUAGCCAGGGCUGGGAACAUAGGAGGUGCUCAGUAAACUAGCUAUGACUAUUAUGUGUUGUAAGCCUUAUUGUUUUUUGAAGAUCUUCCCUAGGCUGGUUGGAGGCUGAGGGGUAAAGAAUGGAUUUGUUGACUAAGGAAGCCUCUGGGAGAGGCUAGACCUUUCAACAGGCCUGCUUCAUAGGCUAUUUAAUGACUUUUAAUAGAUUCUGAGCUUCUGUCCUUGGAGGGGUAGUGAGGGAGCUGGGUCUCUGUUCAUAAACAACUUGUUGAUGCCAUGUGGGCUUGGGGGCAUUGGGCUGUUCAUUGGCGGAAGAGUCUGUCCACUAUCUCUGCCUUGCAGUGGACUCAGAUCAGCAUGUCCUGGGAAAGCUAUAGGCAAGGUGCUGAGGGAAGGUGAGUUUGAAUGAUAGAUUCUAGGCCUCCCCCAAAAGGUAUCUGCCAUGUGCCCAGGUAUAAAGAUAUGGCCUCUUGUACUUGUUUCCAGGAAUACCUGACAGUACCCAUUGGGAGAUCAUAGGUUCUAUGCCCUGAGCCAGUUGGAUGCCUCUAAUAAGGGGAUGGAGGUUUUGAAACAGGCUGUAGUCCAGAGGGCAUGUUUGGAGGCUGGGCUGUGAAUCAUUAGGCAGGCACUACACAGUGCCUCUACACGUACUGUUCUUUCUGCUGGAUAUUCAUCGGACUGGCAGUUUGCUCAUCUUUCCGAACAGCCUAGUUGUUUCCUAUUCUACUCCCAAAGCAAAAUCAGUUCUUCAUCUGUACUCUCAAAGUACUAUGUGAAGAGUGCUACUUCAGCUUCUAAAUAUUGCAUUGUGAUUCCUUUGUGCAUUUGGCUGCUGUUUUCUCAAGCCAUGUUUAUCUUUGUAUUCCCGGAGCUUGUCAUUUGAGAUAUAGCCAGUGUACUUAUUCACCUAGGGAGAGAUAAGGAAUGACAGGGUCCAGUUGAGUGGGAUAGAUGAGAACAGGGGUGUUAUAGAAACCCAGGUACUAGGGCACAAGAUGAGGGCACUGUUGACUAGUCAUGAUGGAAGAAGUAGGCAGACAGGAGAACUUCAUUAGGUAGAAUUGGUGGGAUGUUGAGGUUGGUAAGAGAGGAAUCUGAAGUAAGUUCCAGGUUGCUCAACUGUGGGUAGGCUGGUGAUGCCAUUCAAAGUGUUGGAUUUUAGGAAGUGGGACAUGCGUGAAAUCUGUGCUGGGGGUCUGGGAAUCAGCAGCCUAGAGGUGGUAAUUAAAGUCAGAAUAGAUGAGAUAUUCAGGGUAAGAUAAUGAGAAGAGAAAAUGGCUCAGAAUAGAACUGAGGAGCAUGUCAUGGAUGGGUAAAGGAAAAUGAAGCAGUGAAGGUGAUGGAAGAGGAGAAGGUUCACCCAGAGAUGUAGGAGUAAAACCAGGAGAGUUAAUUUUUUUUUUUUUUUUUUUUUAAGACAGAGUCUUGCUCUGUGGCCCAGGCUGGAAUGCGGUGGCGUGAUCUCAGGUCACUGAAACCUCUGCCUGCUGGUUCAAGCACUUCUCCUGCCUCAGACUCCCGAGUAGCUGGGAAUACAGGCACAUGCCACCACGCCCAGCUAAUUUUUGUAUUUUUAGUAGUGACGGGGUUUCACCAUGUUGGCCAGGCUGGUCUCGAACUCCUGACCUCGAGUGAUCGGCCUGCCUCGGCCUCCCAAAGUGCUGGGAUUACAGGCAUGAGCCACUGUGCCCAGCCAGUGUUUUUUUUUUUUUUUUUUUUAUGGGAGGAUGGGCAGGUUGUUAGCUGUCGAGUGCUAUUGAGAUGAGAGAGAACUCAGAAUGCAGUGGGGUAAGGAUUGCUGAGUAAUGUGGAGGGCCUGUUUGAGGUAAAUGGCAGUGGUAAGAGGUUGCUCCAUUAUGAAAGCCCUCUUCCAGAGUUCCUGAUAGGGCCCCAGAAGUUCAUUUCUGAUUGCUUUGAUUUUUUUUCAGGGGAGCAGGAAGCCAGUUUAUCAUUUGAGAGUGAGAAUAGGGGAGAGGAAAUAUCUUCCAGGCCCACAGUGCAUAGAAAUACCCAGUCAGGGCAAAAUGAUUUAUCUGUUUACCUCUCCUCAUCACUUGGGCCCAGAGCAAUCAGCAGUGAUUAGGUAGAGAGGAGCCGAGCAGAGGGAAGAGCAUACCAAUCACUCCUCCCUUUCCCAGUGCAGGCUCCUAGACUUAGCUGGGGCAGAGCUGGGAGAGGAAAAAGGGAUUUAAAACUGCAACAGGUGCAGAUUAUUGUUACACAGGAUUAGACAUUCUAAUUAAUUGAGAUUAUGUUUGUUCCUUAAACUGAUCACAGGACUAUCUAUUAAGAACAUCACAACCUCGCUGCAGCUUUUCUCCAUAGCAGGGAGAGUACCUCCCAGUGAAUAAAAUUUGGAGGGUGGUAAGAGACAAGAAUAAAAUUGGGUUUGGUUAUCCGUGCCUCAUGCUUGUUCAGCAUCCCUUUGAGAGUUCUCCAAAUAAAUAGUUACUGCUUCUGCAGUUAUUGGUGUGCUCCAGCUUCUGUUCCCAUAAUAUAGUCCAGUCCUAAGGGAACACAGUUCUAAAAGAAACAACAUGAUCUUGGCAGAGACACCGCUCAGCUCCAAACCCAACCAUUUAUGUAACUGCACAAAACUCUCUACAGCUUUUCACAGAGACCAGUAAUUAGAACCUUUCAUCCCCUGGUCAUCCUCCUUCCCAGGUGAAUUCUCUGACCAGCCAUCUGGUUUUAGGAUACCCAACUCCUGCAGUAACUGCCUUACUGGUGGUCUAAUUGCUUCUACUCGUGUCCCUAAAGCAAUUAAUUUUCCACACAGCCAUGUGAUCUUUUUAAAAUGUAAAUCAGCUUAUGUCACUUCUCUGCUUAAAAUCCUUCAAUGGAUUCUCACUGCCUCGAGAACAAAAGACAAACUUUUCAGGCCCCGUGUGAUCUUGCCCAGGCCUCCGUCACCAUCACCAUCUGCAUCUUAACCCACUCCUCCCCUUUCACAAAACUCCAGCCACACAGACUUGCUUUUUAUUCCUCAAGCUUUCCAAACUGUUUCUACUGAGAGUCUUUGCACAUGCUCCAUCUUCCUUGAAUACUCUUUCCCCAGUGAGCUCAUUUUCAUCUUCCUGAAUUCAUACCACUAUUACCUUUGCUUCUGUGGAAGAAACUGGCCAGAUGCUCACCCAAAUGUCCUCUUUCUGGACACAGGUAAACUGCAUUUCCCAGCUCCAUGCAUCUAGGCCUAUGUGAGUAGUUCUCAACAGUGGAAAAUGAGUGGAAGUGAUGUUUCAAUACUAGACCAAGGCAGUUAAAGGGUGGCUGAGCCAUUUCCAUUAUUCUCUUCCUCCUUCCUCUUCAAGGUAACCUUGAAGCACAUGUUUUGACGGUGAUGGAGUCAUAGCAUAGAAGAAGUCUGAAUACCUGAGUUACUAUUUAGGGCAUAAUAGCUACUUGACCAAAAACAUCCAUAUUGGACUUUGAACAAGAAAAUAAACUUGAUUACAUUCUGCUAGUGAGUUUUGAGGGUGUUUUAGCAGUUAUCAUUAUAUACACUGGAUAUAUCUUCUAUGGUAUCCUGUCCACCUUACUCUUGACCACAGUACCCUCUUUGUUUCCUUCAGGGUGUUUCAGAUAUUUAAUUAUCUUGCCAGAUGCCAGUCAACACUUUCUUUUUGUCCCAUGAGUUUAAAAUCAGGGGAAAACAUGUACUCCCAAUAGGAAGUUGAGAUACUCUUUUUUUUUUAAAUCCGUCAUUGUGACUGUGACCGGAAAAACAAAUCCCACUAAAGAAUGUCCUAAACAGAUGUUUUUUUUUGUCAUAUAACCUGGAGUUAGGUGAUUUGGCAUUGGUUCUGGAGCUGAAGGAUGUUAGGGAUGAGGUCUCUGUAGUUUUCUUGUCUCAUGGUCACGAAAUGAAGUGUUAUUGAUUAAGCAGGGAUGCCCUACUUAGUAUUAGACUUCUUGGAAGUCUCCUUAAUUGCCACAGCCCCUAUCUUUUUGGCUUCGUUUCAAGGGUCCUUCUACAUUGUUAAUACUCUGGUAUAAAUACGUUCCAUUAUUCCCUAUAACAUGACUGAAACCAAUCUAAAGUAUUAACAUUUUAAAUAUGUUUUUGGGCCAAGUGCAGUGGCUCUUAUCUGUGAUCCCAGCUACUAGGAAGGCUGAGGUGGGAGGAUUGCUUGAGCCCAGGAAUUUCAGGCUGUAGUGAGCUAUGAUUGUGCCACUGUACUCCGGCCUGGAUAACUGAGAUCCUGUCUCAAUAAAUAAAUAAAACAAUUAUA